GGAGGAGGCGGGCCGUGGCAUACACAGGGCGGCGAGAGCGCGCAGUGCCGGGGCCAGAGCGGCGCGCCCCCUCCUCCCCGCCCCGCCUCGCCGCUAUCCCGCGCCCGGAACCUUGGGCGCGCGGAACCUCGGUGCCGGAGCGCGGGCGCGGCGCACUCGGAGCGGGAUGGAGCGGGCGCGCGGGCCGCGGGCCGAGGCCGACGCGCCUGAGGAGGAGGAGGAGGCGGGGGCGGCCAUGGCUGCUGUGGUGGUGGCGGCUGCGGGUGGCGCGGGACCGGCGGUCCUGCAGGUGGCCGGUCUCUACCGGGGCCUGUGCGCGGUGCGCAGCCGCGCCCUGGGCCUGGGGCUCGUGUCACCCGCGCAGCUGCGCGUCUUCCCAGUGCGCCCCGGCUCGGGCCGGCCCGAGGGGGGCGCCGACAGCAGCGGGGUCGGGGCCGAGGCCGAGCUCCAGGCCAACCCUUUCUACGACCGCUACCGCGACAAGAUCCAGCUGCUGCGCAGGUCAGACCCAGCUGCUUUUGAGUCCCGCCUGGAGAAACGCAGUGAAUUUCGGAAGCAGCCAGUGGGGCAUUCCAGGCAAGGUGAUUUUAUCAAAUGUGUGGAACAGAAGACAGAUGCCUUGGGGAAACAGUCUGUGAACAGAGGAUUCACUAAGGACAAGACUCUCAGUUCAAUCUUUAACAUUGAGAUGGUAAAAGAAAAAACUGCAGAAGAAAUAAAACAGAUUUGGCAGCAAUAUUUUGCAGCAAAAGAUACAGUCUACGCAGUUAUUCCUGCAGAAAAGUUUGAUUUGAUCUGGAACCGGGCUCAGUCCUGUCCAACAUUUCUAUGUGCUCUGCCAAGAAGGGAAGGUUAUGAGUUUUUUGUAGGACAAUGGACAGGUACUGAACUCCACUUCACUGCACUUAUAAAUAUUCAGACCCGAGGGGAAGCUGCAGCCAGCCAGCUGAUUUUAUAUCACUAUCCUGAACUUAAGGAAGAAAAGGGCAUAGUGCUGAUGACUGCAGAAAUGGAUUCCACAUUUCUGAAUGUUGCUGAGGCACAGUGCAUCGCCAACCAAGUUCAGCUCUUCUACGCUACUGAUCGGAAAGAGACCUACGGGUUAGUGGAGACCUUUAACCUCAGACCAAAUGAGUUCAAAUAUAUGUCUGUCAUCGCUGAAUUGGAGCAAAGCGGACUUGGAGCAGAACUGAAAUGUGCCCAGAACCAAAAUAAGACUUAGAACUGUACAGGUUGGCCCUUCACCUAGUUGACUCAGCCCUCGAUAGUCUAGAGCCCACCCCCUCCUCAGGAACUCAAGAGCUCAGCAUUUAUAAUGAGCAGUUGGUAAUGAGUUGCCCUAUGUGCUUGUCGCAAGCAGUCACAGAGAUGAGCCCUAUUACUUGAUAUUCAGGAACAAAGGUACCUGAACAUUCUGAUAAUUAUCUCAGCAUACUUGAGGUUUCCUUUUUUAAGUGUUCGAGGUUAUAACAAGAGACAGCCAAGGACCUACAAGACAGUUGACUUGAUUUUGCACAGUGUAACAGCGCAGUUGCAUUCUGGCCACUUUGACCUUAUAGCUCCCAAAUGAUGAGUUUGUCAUCUUUAUGAACUCAUGACAGGAUAAUAAGCUUGAAGACCUGCUGUAGUUAGAUAUGGGCUUUAAUCCUUCCCAGGCACCAGUCAGCUGAACAAAAGCAUAAGCCAAACAUCCUGUUUAAACUGUAGAAUAACCAGAUAUUCCCAUCAGGUUAAAGACUUCAUCUAGAUGAUGCCCCCCAGAGAUGCCUUUAGUGUAAGUAGCUGGCUUGGGGUAUCAGCAAAUUUCAGGUAUAGUUAGAUAAACAGGUACAGGGCCUGCAUACUAUUAAACCAUAGUUUGUGGCACCCGCUUUUCUAACUCCACCUGUUAGAAGCUAUGUGUUUGAAGGAAUGAAUCAGUGCAGUAUAAAUAAAAUUCUUUUGUAAGGAGAAGAUUAAUCCUGGUUUGCAUGAUUUUUUUAAAAACAACUCUAAACAUGAUACGAAAAAGUGGAUGAAAGCAAAUGUUCCCAGAUUGGAUGUGGGGAAAAUAUAGCAAUAAUUUUUUUUUUAAGUCUGGCUUACAAUGUUUGUUAUACAAAAUAAUGAAAUCUGAGUUAUGUACUGUCCAUUGUGUCAGGGCUAUGGGCUGAUUUUAUCAAAACUCAUCUUGGGACUGAAAAAUUGUUUGGAAUGCCAGAAAUAAGAAAGUUGUUCUCCAGAGCUGGAAACCCAUCUUUCGUUUGUAGUGUCACUGUUGUGGCUCCAAGCUCAGUGAUAGGAAAGGACGGUGGUUACACACCAGCCUUCUGAACCCAAGGCCCCCAGUAUUGUUGUCAGCUGCCUUUACCAUGGCAUUUCUUUCUCUUUCUUUUUUUCCUGAGAUGAAGUCUUGCUCUGUCUUGCCCAGGCUGGAGUACAGUAGCGUGAUCUCAGCUCGCUGCAACCUCUACCUCCCUGGUUCAAGUGAUUCUGCUGCGUCAGCCUCCUGAGGAGCUAGGAUUACAGGCGCAUGCCACCAUACCUGGCUUAUUUUUGUAUUGUUGUAGAGACAGGGUUUCACUUUGUUGGCCAGGCUGGCUGGUCUCGAACUCCUGGCCUCAAGUGAUCCACCACCUUGGCCUCCCAAAGUGCUGGGAUUACAGGUGUGAGCCACCGUGCCUGGCCUGACAUUUCUUUAUUGAUCUAACAUGCUCCACUCUGCUGCUCCUGCCUAAGAUCUGGUUAUAUGACACUGAAUGUGGUGAGUGGGAAUUUAAGCAGUAUUCGCAGUUUGUGUGUGUGUGUUUUCUUCCUUCCAGAAGAAUUUUUAUAGGUUGGGCCUGUCCCUAAGCUCUUUAAAUAGGGUGGACAUCCCACUAUUCUCUGAGCCGUGUCUAUUUUGUUGCACCUUUGAGUCUAUGUAUUGAGAGAGACAGAUAGUAUUUUUUUAAACUGGGGAAGCUGCUAUCCUUUCACUAUUUCUCUAAAGGUUGAGCUGUUAACUAAUGUAAAUUCUGGACCUGCUUCUGGUCCUGGCAGUUUAUCUUUUGAGAAACUUGAGUCUUAUCUGCCCUGCCAUUUUCAUUAAAUGCCUUCUGACCUUCUGAAUGUUUUGGGUCCCAAGAAUUUUUGACAUCAGAUGGGGUUGUUUUUAUUGGUAUCCAGUUAUGUUUGCUUGUCUUUCCAGAUGGGCCCAGUUAUUAGCCAUACAUAGUACAUUGAUACACCUCCACCAGCGGGUGAGGAAAUGAUGGAAAAAGGAGUAAGAAGUGGCCAUUCGUUUUAAUCAUUCCUCCUGGAUUUGUCCUCAGUCCCCAACUGCCAAGUAGGAUGUGUCCAUGGAUAAAUGUGUGGGGCAUGACUAAAGUACCACGUAGCUGUUCUUUAUAUUUAUUUACCUAGAAAGAUCUGGCAAAGAACUCAAAGAAAAUUGUACCAUUUAAUCAGUAAAUUUGUCCCCUGGUGCUAGCAUGGUGUUAUAGAAAGUGGACAGGCUUUAGAGUUAAGUGAAUCUGGGUUCAUAUGUUAGUGUUGCUAUUCAUUAGCUCUAUACUGUUGAACAAAUUGCUUAAACUAUCUAAUUUUGGGGUUUUUUUUCCAUCUAAAAUAGGGAUAAUAAUAUCUACCUCAUAGGAUUAUUGUGAGAAUUAAAUUAACUUCACUAUAGUAGAAAAUAUCAACUACCAUCCUUUUCUCUACUUCCCUUGCCCCUCAUUAAAGACUAAUACAAGUUAGCAUUUCAGAUGUGUAGAUCAUUCUUUAUUCCAGUUAAAAGAACAAACUUUAUCUCAUCAGUUCUGAAACUUUAAGAUGCAGUAGCAUCACCUAAAGUGCUUUUAAAAUGCAGAUUCUCAGGCCUCAACCGUACACCACCCCCCCACACACGUACUAAAUCAAGAAUAUGUGCAGAAGGUACUGGGAAUCUACUUGUUAAUAUGUGCUCCAAAUGAUUCUGAUGUAGGUAAUUAGCCAGCCACACUUUGAGAACCACUGCCUUAUCUAUUCUUUACAAAAAUGUACAUUGCCAGGUCUUUCUUUCCUGUGGAUGCUAACUAUAGGAUAUUUAGGUUCCUCUGUUCUUUGUCUCCCAUAGUGGCCCCCUUUGCAAACUCCAAAUACAUUAUAUUUAUUUAUUCUUGUGUCUUUUUUCCCCCACUAGACUGUGAGCUCCUUGAGGGCCAGGACUUAUCUCUGUUCGCAGUGCCAAGGACAUGGCCUGGACCAUAGAAGAUACUCAGUUUUUUGUUGAAUAAAUAGGUAAUAUGGAUUUCAACCAAAA